AGUUCGCGACAGGACGAGCGGAAAUACUGCCAGGAUUUUACCACCUCUCGCCCAUUUAUUUACUUCUCGGUCACCGCUUUCGGGGGACAGAUAAACACCACAGAUGCCCAUCAAAGGGGCGCACGGGUCUGGAGGCGCAGCUCAGGUUUUUGCGUUGGUCACCCUGCCCUCCGCACGUGGAGAGGGCAGGCAUAAAGCACCUUGAAAGGAAGGUGCUGUCAAUGCUAUCCGACGACCUGUCGCCGGGCACCGCAGCAUCCUCGCUCGCUCCGAUGGGACGAGGGACGCCGGCCCCAGGGUAACAGGAGGCGCCUCGCCGGCCGCGCGCUGGAUGCUGUGAUCCAGGUCCGGAGCCGGGUUCCGCCGCGGCCGCAGCGACCCGACCCCACCCGACAGGCCAGAGGAAUCAGUUUAGACUUGAAAUUCAGUUUUUCCUGAAACUGAUCAGAAGUUAGUGACACCUUGAUUGGAUCCGUUUUUCUGUCAGGAGCUCAUUUUGCAGCUCUCAAGCUUUUAUAGCAUGCUGUAAACAAUUGUCAAAGUUGUUUAUCAAGAAACAGAUAGAGUUGCAACUUGUUUCUAGUAAUAGAAACUUUUACACUGCAUUCAAUGCCUAACGUUGCAGAAACAGAAAGGUCAAAUGAUUCUGGAAAUGGUGAGCACAAAUCUGAGAGAAAGUCACCUGAAGAGAAUCUACAAGGUGCUGUAAAAUCUUUCUGCACAAGUGCCUCAGGAGCACCCUUGGGUCCCAAAGGAGAUGGUCAUUAUCCAUGGAGUUGUCCAGUGACUCAUACACGGGAAAAAAUUUAUGCCAUCUGUUCGGACUAUGCCUUUCUCAACCAGGCGACCUCAAUCUAUAAAACUCCAAAUCCAUCCCGCUCUCCUUGCCUCCCUGAUAGUACCUCUUUAUCUGCUGGAAAUAAUUCAUCAAGAUACAUUGGUAUCCCGACUAGUACAUCGGAAAUUAUCUACAAUGAAGAAAAUAGCUUGGAAAACUUAUCCAACAGCCUGGGCAAGCUACCUCUCGCAUGGGAAAUUGAUAAAUCUGAAUUUGAUGGGGUGACCACAAAUUCGAAACACAAAUCAGGCAAUGCAAAGAAACAAGUUUCCAAGAGAAAAACUUCAGAUAAAAAGGGAAGAUAUCAGAAGGAAUGUCCUCAGCAUUCUCCUCUUGAAGAUAUUAAACAGCGGAAAGUAUUAGACCUCAGACGAUGGUACUGCAUAAGCCGACCACAGUAUAAGACUUCUUGUGGCAUCUCUUCAUUAAUUUCUUGUUGGAAUUUCUUAUACAGCACAAUGGGAGCUGGAAACCUUCCACCUAUUACCCAAGAAGAAGCUUUACAUAUUCUGGGCUUUCAACCUCCAUUUGAAGAUAUUAGGUUUGGUCCUUUCACGGGGAAUACAACACUUAUGAGGUGGUUUAGACAAAUUAAUGACCACUUCCAUGUAAAAGGAUGCUCUUAUGUUCUAUAUAAGCCUCAUGGGAAGAAUAAAACAGCAGGAGAAACUGCUUCAGGGGCCCUGUCAAAGUUAACCCGUGGAUUGAAAGAUGAAUCGCUGGCUUAUAUCUAUCAUUGCCAAAAUCAUUAUUUUUGUCCAAUUGGCUUCGAAGCAACCCCUGUUAAAGCUAAUAAAGCAUUCAGCAGGGGACCUCUCUCACCACAGGAAGUUGAAUAUUGGAUCUUAAUUGGAGAAUCAAGUAGAAAACAUCCUGCCAUUCACUGUAAAAAAUGGGCAGAUAUUGUUACUGAUCUAAACACUCAAAAUCCAGAAUACCUGGAUAUCCGGCACUUAGAGAGGGGACUGCAGUAUAGAAAAACAAAGAAGGUUGGGGGAAAUUUGCAUUGCAUCAUAGCAUUCCAGAGACUUAACUGGCAAAGAUUUGGCCUUUGGAACUUUCCAUUUGGAACCAUUAGACAAGAAUCACAACCUCCAACACAUGCCCAGGGAAUUGCCAAAUCUGAGAGUGAAGACAAUAUUUCCAAGAAGCAGCAUGGGCGUCUGGGCCGGUCUUUCAGUGCUAGUUUCCAUCAGGACUCGGCAUGGAAAAAGAUGUCUAGUAUCCAUGAGAGAAGGAACAGUGGUUACCAGGGUUACAGUGAUUACGAUGGGAAUGAUUGACUAUGCUUGCUACUGAACAGCUGGCAUUAUAUAUGAAACUGCUAUAUACAGGACUGUAUAAAGACAGUAGAAGAUUUUAGUAAGCCUACAUUAAAUAGGAGCAGAUCUUGUGGUAUAAAAAAUAACCUUGUAGUUCUCCAGAUACUAAGCUUGUAUAUGAUUAUGGUGGGUGAUUUCAGAUAUAUAAGCAGAUAAGCACAGAUUAUUGUCCUUUCAAGUUAAGAGUAUAUAAUCUGGACAGAAAAUUUCACAAAAUUCAAUAAAAUUACAACUGUUGUCUAAAUAAGUGAAACACAAAUUCACUUAAUAGCAUCAAGAUUUGAAAUACUUAAGCAUGAAGUGACUUUUAUAAUGACUCGAUCCCUAGACAUUUGUUACAGAUAGUUUUAUGCCUAAGACCAAGAUGUAAAGUACCAUCUGCCCUUAAAAAAAAUUGGGGCUGUCAAUUUCUAGUUUUCACUCAUGGUUAACACGCAUUUAAAAUUAUUUCAUGAGUCUAGUAGUUCUUUGAUUUAUAGCAGGAUCUUGCUUGCCUCAUUUGUUUCCUGGUUAUGUUCUUAGGAUUCUGACUAAGAGGCAAAAGAGAAAAGACUCAAGAAACUGAUCCUGGAGAUCGAGACCAUCCUGGCUAACAUGGUGAAACCCCGUCUCUACUAAACAUACAAAAAAUUAGCCGGGUGUAGUGGUGGGCACCUGUAGUCCUAGCUACUCGAGAGGCUGAGGCAGGAGAAUGGCGUGAACCCGGGAGGUGGAGCUUGCAGUGAGCGGAGAUCGCGCCACUGCACUCCAGCCUGGGCGACAGGGCAAGACUCUGUCUCAAAAAAAAAAAAAAAAAAAAAGACGGAUCCUUUUUUUUGGUGCAAAUGGGUGACUUAGUGCAUUGAUUCAGAUUUUUAAAAUUUCUUGAUGUGGUUUGUAAUAAUCAAAUAUUGACAAGAACCUUAGGUCUCGAAAGACUUUUAUAAGUCUAGAUGACGUUUGCCUUAGGGGUAAAGUAAAAGAACAAUUGGCACCUUAAGUUUCUAUACCCAAGGUUAUCUGUGAAAUGAGAUCUCCUGAUAUUUGAUUGCUUUCUCAGUAUGGAGUCAUAUGUUGAUAACAGUACUGAAGAUGCAUAAGAAAUGCCCAAGUCACUCAGAGGACAACUACCCAUAUUCCAGACUCUGAGCUGUUUCCUUUUUAAAAAUCAUAUAGACAAUUAGCUGUUUGAAGUGAGUAUUAAAUAUUUCAGAAGUGUGAAUUUCAUGUAUUUGAGCUCCUCUAGUUGCUGUUGGUUUUUCUUCUGCUGCCAACCUGUGACUCACAAAUGACUAGGAUCUCUUGUUCUUUAAUUUUAGGGUCUUGUUCCAGGACUCAAAUCAGUAACUUGGUGAUUACAAGGUGCUGAAUGUGUUGGUAACCAUAUCGCAAUACACCUCAAGGAAAAGGUUCAGAUUUUUAUUUUUAAAAUAUUUUCAUUUUUUUCUUGAAUUUUAUAUCCGUUUGUUCACUCGUACAUGCCUAGCCUACAGAAGGGGAUAUAUAUUAUGAAAUGGUCAUUUUUCUGAAGAGAAUAUUUUGCUUGAAAUGCAAAGGACUGAAAGAGAUUUGUAGGUUGUUGAUUUUGUUACUUCAUACUGGAACUUUUAAAAAGAUUUCAUCAAAUAAAGUUUUGUUUUCUACUUUUAA